ACUCCCUGAGGUCUGUCCUGGGGAGACACUGCUGCUCCGGGGGGCUGACCUGGCGGGGAGUGGCCGCGCAGUCUGCUCCGGCGCCGCUUUGUGCGCGCAGCCGCUGGCCCCUCUACUCCCGGGUCUGCCCCCCGGGACACCCCUCUGCCUCGCCCAAGUCAUGCAGCCCUACCUGCCUCUCCACUGUGGACCUUUGGGAACCGACUCCUCACCUCGGGGGCUCGGGCCUUGACUGUGCUGGGAGCCGGUAGGCGUCCUCCGCGACCCGCCCGCGCCCCUCGCGCCCGCCGGGGCCCCGGGCUCCAAAGUUGUGGGGACCGGCGCGAGUUGGAAAGUUUGCCCGAGGGCUGGUGCAGGCUUGGAGCUGGGGGCCGUGCGCUGCCCUGGGAAUGUGACCCGGCCAGCGACCAAAACCUUGUGUGACUGAGCUGAAGAGCAGUGCAUCCAGAUUCUCCUCAGAAGUGAGACUUUCCAAAGGACCAAUGACUCUGUUUCCUGCGCCCUUUCAUUUUUUCCUACUCUGUAGCUAUGUCUCGAUCCCGCCAUGCAAGGCCUUCCAGAUUAGUCAGGAAGGAAGAUGUAAACAAAAAAAAGAAAAACAGCCAACUACGAAAGACAACCAAGGGAGCCAACAAAAAUGUGGCAUCAGUCAAGACUUUAAGCCCUGGAAAAUUAAAGCAAUUAAUUCAAGAAAGAGAUGUUAAGAAAAAAACAGAACCUAAACCACCCGUGCCAGUCAGAAGCCUUCUGACAAGAGCUGGAGCAGCACGCAUGAAUUUGGAUAGGACUGAGGUUCUUUUUCAGAACCCAGAGUCCUUAACCUGCAAUGGGUUUACAAUGGCGCUACGAAGCACCUCUCUUAGCAGGCGACUCUCCCAACCCCCACUGGUCGUAGCCAAAUCCAAAAAGGUUCCACUUUCUAAGGGUUUAGAAAAGCAACAUGAUUGUGAUUAUAAGAUACUCCCUGCUUUGGGAGUAAAGCACUCAGAAAAUGAUUCGGUUCCAAUGCAAGACACCCAAGUCCUUCCUGAUAUAGAGACUCUAAUUGGUGUACAAAAUCCCUCUUUACUUAAAGGUAAGAGCCAAGAGACAACUCAGUUUUGGUCCCAAAGAGUUGAGGAUUCCAAGAUCAAUAUCCCUACCCACAGUGGCCCUGCAGCUGAGAUCCUUCCUGGGCCACUGGAAGGGACACGCUGUGGUGAAGGACUAUUCUCUGAAGAGACAUUGAAUGAUACCAGUGGUUCCCCAAAAAUGUUUGCUCAGGACACAGUGUGUGCUCCUUUUCCCCAAAGAGCAACCCCCAAAGUUACCUCUCAAGGAAACCCCAGCAUUCAGUUAGAAGAGUUGGGUUCACGAGUAGAAUCUCUUAAGUUAUCUGAUUCUUACCUGGAUCCCAUUAAAAGUGAACAUGAUUGCUACCCCACCUCCAGUCUUAAUAAGGUUAUACCUGACUUGAACCUUAGAAACUGCUUGGCUCUUGGUGGGUCUACGUCUCCUACCUCUGUAAUAAAAUUCCUCUUGGCAGGCUCAAAACAAGCGACCCUUGGUGCUAAACCAGAUCAUCAAGAGGCCUUCGAAGCUACUGCAAAUCAACAGGAAGUUUCUGAUACCACCUCUUUCCUAGGACAGGCCUUUGGUGCUAUCCCACAUCAAUGGGAACUUCCUGGUGCUGACCCAGUUCAUGGUGAGGCCCUGGGUGAGACCCCAGAUCUACCAGAGAUUCCUGGUGCUAUUCCAGUCCAAGGAGAGGUCUUUGGUACUAUUUUAGACCAACAAGAAACUCUUGGUAUGAGUGGGAGUGUUGUCCCAGACUUGCCUGUCUUCCUUCCUGUUCCUCCAAAUCCAAUUGCUACCUUUAAUGCUCCUUCCAAAUGGCCUGAGCCCCAAAGCACUGUCUCAUAUGGACUUGCAGUCCAGGGUGCUAUACAGAUUUUGCCUUUGGGCUCAGGACACACUCCUCAAUCAUCAUCAAACUCAGAGAAAAAUUCAUUACCUCCAGUAAUGGCUAUAAGCAAUGUAGAAAAUGAGAAGCAGGUUCAUAUAAGCUUCCUGCCAGCUAACACUCAGGGGUUCCCAUUAGCCCCUGAGAGAGGACUCUUCCAUGCUUCACUGGGUAUAGCCCAACUCUCUCAGGCUGGUCCUAGCAAAUCAGACAGAGGGAGCUCCCAGGUCAGUGUAACCAGCACAGUUCAUGUUGUCAACACCACAGUGGUGACUAUGCCAGUGCCAAUGGUCAGUACCUCCUCUUCUUCCUAUACCACUUUGCUACCGACUUUGGAAAAGAAGAAAAGAAAGCGAUGUGGGGUCUGUGAACCCUGCCAGCAGAAGACCAACUGUGGUGAAUGCACUUACUGCAAGAACAGAAAGAACAGCCAUCAGAUCUGUAAGAAAAGAAAAUGUGAGGAGCUGAAAAAGAAACCAUCUGUUGUUGUGCCUCUGGAGGUUAUAAAGGAAAACAAGAGGCCCCAGAGGGAAAAGAAGCCCAAAGUUUUAAAGGCAGAUUUUGACAACAAACCAGUAAAUGGCCCCAAGUCAGAAUCCAUGGACUACAGUAGAUGUGGUCAUGGGGAAGAACAAAAAUUGGAAUUGAACCCACAUACUGUUGAAAAUGUAACUAAAAAUGAAGACAGCAUGACAGGCAUCGAGGUGGAGAAGUGGACACAAAACAAGAAAUCACAGUUAACUGAUCACGUGAAAGGAGAUUUUAGUGCUAAUGUCCCAGAAGCUGAAAAAUCGAAAAACUCUGAAGUUGACAAGAAACGAACCAAAUCUCCAAAAUUGUUUGUACAAACCGUAAGAAAUGGCAUUAAACAUGUACACUGUUUACCAGCUGAAACAAAUGUUUCAUUUAAAAAAUUCAAUAUUGAAGAAUUCGGCAAGACAUUGGAAAACAAUUCUUAUAAAUUCCUAAAAGACACUGCAAACCAUAAAAACGCUAUGAGCUCUGUUGCUACUGAUAUGAGUUGUGAUCAUCUCAAGGGGAGAAGUAACGUUUUAGUAUUCCAGCAGCCUGGCUUUAACUGCAGUUCCAUUCCACAUUCUUCACACUCCAUCAUAAAUCAUCAUGCUAGUAUACACAAUGAAGGUGAUCAACCAAAAACUCCUGAGAAUAUACCAAGUAAAGAACCAAAAGAUGGAUCUCCCGUUCAACCAAGUCUCUUAUCGUUAAUGAAAGAUAGGAGAUUAACAUUGGAGCAAGUGGUAGCCAUAGAGGCCCUGACUCAACUCUCAGAAGCCCCAUCAGAGAAUUCCUCCCCAUCAAAGUCAGAGAAGGAUGAGGAAUCAGAGCAGAGAACAGCCAGUUUGCUUAAUAGCUGCAAAGCUAUCCUCUACACUGUAAGAAAAGACCUCCAAGACCCAAACUUACAGGGAGAGCCACCAAAACUUAAUCACUGUCCAUCUUUGGAAAAACAAAGUUCAUGCAACACGGUGGUUUUCAAUGGGCAAACUACUACCCUUUCCAACUCACAUAUCAACUCAGCUACUAACCAAGCAUCCACAAAGUCACAUGAAUAUUCAAAAGUCACAAAUUCAUUAUCUCUUUUUAUACCAAAAUCAAAUUCAUCCAAGAUUGACACCAAUAAAAGUAUUGCUCAAGGGAUAAUUACUCUUGACAAUUGUUCCAAUGAUUUGCAUCAGUUGCCACCAAGAAAUAAUGAAGUGGAGUAUUGCAACCAGUUACUGGACAGCAGCAAAAAAUUGGACUCAGAUGAUCUAUCAUGUCAGGAUGCAACCCAUACCCAAAUUGAGGAAGAUGUUGCAACACAGUUGACACAACUUGCUUCGAUAAUUAAGAUCAAUUAUAUAAAACCAGAGGACAAAAAAGUUGAAAGUACACCAACAAGCCUUGUCACAUGUAAUGUACAGCAAAAAUACAAUCAGGAGAAGGGCACAAUACAACAGAAACCACCUUCAAGUGUACACAAUAAUCAUGGUUCAUCAUUAACAAAACAAAAGAACCCAACCCAGAAAAAGACAAAAUCCACCCCAUCAAGAGAUCGGCGGAAAAAGAAGCCCACAGUUGUAAGUUAUCAAGAAAAUGAUCGGCAGAAGUGGGAAAAGUUGUCCUAUAUGUAUGGCACAAUAUGCGACAUUUGGAUAGCAUCGAAAUUUCAAAAUUUUGGGCAAUUUUGUCCACAUGAUUUUCCUACUGUAUUUGGGAAAAUUUCUUCCUCGACCAAAAUAUGGAAACCACUGGCUCAAACGAGGUCCAUUAUGCAACCCAAAACAGUAUUUCCACCACUCACUCAGAUAAAAUUACAGAGAUAUCCUGAAUCAGCAGAGGAAAAGGUGAAGGUUGAACCAUUGGAUUCACUCAGCUUAUUUCAUCUUAAAACGGAAUCCAACGGGAAGGCAUUCACUGAUAAAGCUUAUAAUUCUCAGGUACAGUUAACGGUGAAUGCCAAUCAGAAAGCCCAUCCUUUGACCCAGCCCUCCUCUCCACCUAACCAGUGUGCUAACGUGAUGGCAGGCGAUGACCAAAUACGGUUUCAGCAGGUUGUUAAGGAGCAACUCAUGCAUCAGAGACUGCCAACAUUGCCUGGUAUCUCUCAUGAAACACCCUUACCGGAGUCAGCACUAACUCUCAGGAAUGUAAAUGUAGUGUGUUCAGGUGGAAUUACAGUGGUUUCUACCAAAAGUGAAGAGGAAGUCUGUUCAUCCAGUUUUGGAACAUCAGAAUUUUCCACAGUGGACAGUGCACAGAAAAAUUUUAAUGAUUAUGCCAUGAACUUCUUUACUAACCCUACAAAAAACCUAGUGUCUAUAACUAAAGAUUCUGAACUGCCCACCUGCAGCUGUCUUGAUCGAGUUAUACAAAAAGACAAAGGCCCAUAUUAUACACACCUUGGGGCAGGACCAAGUGUUGCUGCUGUCAGGGAAAUCAUGGAGAAUAGGUAUGGUCAAAAAGGAAACGCAAUAAGGAUAGAAAUAGUAGUGUACACCGGUAAAGAAGGGAAAAGCUCUCAUGGGUGUCCAAUUGCUAAGUGGGUUUUAAGAAGAAGCAGUGAUGAAGAAAAAGUUCUUUGUUUGGUCCGGCAGCGUACAGGCCACCACUGUCCAACUGCUGUGAUGGUGGUGCUCAUCAUGGUGUGGGAUGGCAUCCCUCUUCCAAUGGCCGACCGGCUAUACACAGAGCUCACAGAGAAUCUAAAGUCAUACAAUGGGCACCCUACCGACAGAAGAUGCACCCUCAAUGAAAAUCGUACCUGUACAUGUCAAGGAAUUGAUCCAGAGACUUGUGGAGCUUCAUUCUCUUUUGGCUGUUCAUGGAGUAUGUACUUUAAUGGCUGUAAGUUUGGUAGAAGCCCAAGCCCCAGAAGAUUUAGAAUUGAUCCAAGCUCUCCCUUACAUACCUACUAUGAAAGAAUUACUAAAGGACGUAAUCCAGAAAGAAGAUAUAUGAAACCGGAACGAAUCAGUCCGGGACACGAGGCCAUGGAAAAAAACCUUGAAGAUAACUUACAGAGUUUGGCUACACGAUUAGCUCCAAUUUAUAAGCAGUAUGCUCCAGUAGCUUACCAAAAUCAGGUGGAAUAUGAAAAUGUUGCCCGAGAAUGUCGGCUUGGCAGCAAGGAAGGUCGUCCCUUCUCUGGGGUCACUGCUUGCCUGGACUUCUGUGCUCAUCCCCACAGGGACAUUCACAACAUGAAUAAUGGAAGCACUGUGGUUUGUACCUUAACUCGAGAAGAUAACCGCUCUUUGGGUGUUAUUCCUCAAGAUGAGCAGCUCCAUGUGCUACCUCUUUAUAAGCUUUCAGACACAGAUGAGUUUGGCUCCAAGGAAGGAAUGGAAGCCAAGAUCAAAUCUGGGGCCAUCGAGGUCCUGGCACCCCGCCGCAAAAAAAGAACGUGUUUCACUCAGCCUGUUCCCCGUUCUGGAAAGAAGAGGGCUGCGAUGAUGACAGAGGUUCUUGCACAUAAGAUAAGGGCAGUGGAAAAGAAACCUAUUCCCCGAAUCAAGCGGAAGAAUAACUCAACAACAACAAACAACAGUAAGCCUUCGUCACUGCCAACCUUAGGGAGUAACACUGAGACCGUGCAACCUGAAGUAAAAAGUGAAACCGAACCCCAUUUUAUCUUAAAAAGUUCAGACAACACUAAAACUUAUUCGCUGAUGCCAUCCGCUCCUCACCCAGUGAAAGAGGCAUCUCCAGGCUUCUCCUGGUCCCCGAAGACUGCUUCAGCCACACCAGCUCCACUGAAGAAUGACGCAACAGCCUCAUGCGGGUUUUCAGAAAGAAGCAGCACUCCCCACUGUACGAUGCCUUCGGGAAGACUCAGUGGUGCCAAUGCAGCUGCUGCUGAUGGCCCUGGCAUUUCACAGCUUGGCGAAGUGGCUCCUCUCCCCACCCUGUCUGCUCCUGUGAUGGAGCCCCUCAUUAAUUCUGAGCCUUCCACUGGUGUGACUGAGCCGCUAACGCCUCAUCAGCCAAACCACCAGCCCUCCUUCCUCACCUCUCCUCAAGACCUUGCCUCUUCUCCAAUGGAAGAAGAUGAGCAGCAUUCUGAAGCAGAUGAGCCUCCAUCAGACGAACCCCUAUCUGAUGACCCCCUGUCACCUGCUGAGGAGAAAUUGCCCCACAUUGAUGAGUAUUGGUCAGACAGUGAGCACAUCUUUUUGGAUGCAAAUAUUGGUGGGGUGGCCAUCGCACCUGCUCACGGCUCGGUUUUGAUUGAGUGUGCCCGGCGAGAGCUGCACGCUACCACUCCUGUUGAGCACCCCAACCGUAAUCAUCCAACCCGCCUCUCCCUUGUCUUUUACCAGCACAAAAACCUAAAUAAGCCCCAACAUGGUUUUGAACUAAACAAGAUUAAGUUUGAGGCUAAAGAAGCUAAGAAUAAGAAAAUGAAGGCCUCAGAGCAAAAAGACCAGGCAGCUAAUGAAGGUCCAGAACAGUCCUCUGAAGUAAAUGAAUUGAACCAAAUUCCUUCUCAUAAAGCAUUAACAUUAACCCAUGACAAUGUUGUCACCGUGUCCCCUUAUGCUCUCACACACGUUGCGGGGCCCUAUAACCAUUGGGUCUGAAGGCUUUUCUCCCCCUCUUAAUGCCUUUGCUAGUGCAGUGUAUUUUUUCAAGGUGCUGUUAAAAGAAAGUCAUGUUGUCGUUUACUAUCUUCAUCUCACCCAUUUCAAGUCUGAGGUAAAAAAAUAAUAAUGAUAACAAAACGGGGUGGGUAUUCUUAACUGUGACUAUAUUUUGACAAUUGGUAGAAGGUGCACAUUUUAAGCAAAAAUAAAAGUUUUAUAGUUUUAAAUACAUAAAGAAAUGUUUCAGUUAGGCAUUAACCUUGAUAGAAUCACUCAGUUUGGUGCUUUAAAUUAAGUCUGUUUACUAUGAAACAAGAGUCAUUUUUAGAGGAUUUUAACAGGUUCAUGUUCUAUGAUGUAAAAUCAAGACACACAGUGUUAACUCUACACAGCUUCUGGUGCUUAACCACAUCCACACAGUUAAAAAUAAGCUGAAUUAUUAUUUCAUGGUGCCAUUGUUCCAACAUCUUCCAAUCAUUGCUAGAAAAUUGGCAUAUUCCUUUGAAAUAAACUUAUGAAAUGUUUUCUCUCUUAAAAUAUUUCUCCUGUGUAAAAUAAAUCAUUGUUGUUAGUAAUGGUUGGAGGCUGUUCAUAAAUUGUAAAUAUAUAUUUUAAAAGCACUUUCUAUUUUUAAAAGUAACUUGAAAUAAUAUAGUAUAAGAAUCCUAUUGUCUAUUGUUUGUGCAUAUUUGCAUACAAGAGAAAUCAUUUAUCCUUGCUGUGUAGAGUUCCAUCUUGUUAACUGCAGUAUGUAUUCUAAUCAUGUAUAUGGUUUGUGUUCUUUUACUGUGUCCUCUCACAUUCAAGUAUUAGCAACUUGCAGUAUAUAAAAUAGUUAGAUAAUGAGAAGUUGUUAAUUAUCUCUAAAAUUGGAAUUAGGAAGCAUAUCACCAAUACUGAUUAACAUUCUCUUUGGAACUAGGUAAGAGUGGUCUCUUCUUAUUGAACAACCUCAAUUUAGUUUCAUCCCACCUUUCUCAGUAUAAUCCAUGAGAGGUGUUUCCAAAAGGAGAUGAGGGAACAGGAUAGGUUUCAGAAGAGUCAAAUGCUUCUAAUGUCUCAAGGUGAUAAAAUACAAAAACUAAGUAGACAGAUAUUUGUACUGAAGUCUGAUACAGAAUUAGAAAAAAAAAAUUCUUGUUGAAAUAUUUUGAAAACAAAUUCCCUACUAUCAUCACAUGCCUCCCCAACCCCAAGUCAAAAACAAGAGGAAUGGUACUACAAACAUGGCUUUGUCCAUUAAGAGCUAAUUCAUUUGUUUAUCUUAGCAUACUAGAUUUGGGAAAAUGAUAACUCAUCUUUUCUGAUAAUUGCCUAUGUUCUAGGUAACAGGAAAACAGGCAUUAAGUUUAUUUUAGUCUUCCCAUUUUCUUCCUAUUACUUUAUUGACUCAUUUUAUUGCAAAACAAAAAGGAUUACCCAAACAACAUGUUUCGAACAAGGAGAAUUUUCAAUGAAAUACUUGAUUCUGUUAAAAUGCAGAGGUGCUAUAACAUUCAAAGUGUCAGAUUCCUUGGGAGUAUGGAAAACCUAAUGGUGCUUCUCCCUUGGAAAUGCCAUAGGAAGCCCACAACCGCUAACACUUACAAUUUUGGUGCAAAAGCAAACAGUUCCAGCAGGCUCUCUAAAGAAAAACUCAUUGUAACUUAUUAAAAUAAUAUCUGGUGCAAAGUAUCUGUUUUGAGCUUUUGACUAAUCCAAGUAAAGGAAUAUGAAGGGAUUGUAAAAAACAAAAUGUCCAUUGAUAGACCAUCGUGUACAAGUAGAUUUCUGCUUGUUGAAUAUGUAAAAUAGGGUAAUUCAUUGACUUGUUUUAGUAUUUUGUGUGCCUUAGAUUUCCGUUUUAAGACAUGUAUAUUUUUGUGAGCCUAAGGUUUCUUAUAUACAUAUAAGUAUAUAAAUAAGUGAUUGUUUAUUGCUUCAGCUGCUUCAACAAGAUAUUUACUAGUAUUAGACUAUCAGGAAUACACCCUUGCGAGAUUAUGUUUUAGAUUUUAGGCCUUAGCUCCCACUAGAAAUUAUUUCUUCACCAGAUUUAAUGGAUAAAGUUUUAUGGCUCUUUAUGCAUCCACUCAUCUACUCAUUCUUCGAGUCUACACUUAUUGAAUGCCUGCAAAAUCUAAGUAUCACUUUUAUUUUUCUUUGGAUCACCACCUAUGACAUAGUAAACUUGAAGAAUAAAAACUACCCUCAGAAAUAUUUUUAAAAGAAGUAGCAAAUUAUCUUCAGUAUAAUCCAUGGUAAUGUAUGCAGUAAUUCAAAUUGAUCUCUCUCUCAAUAGGUUUCUUAACAAUCUAAACUUGAAACAUCAAUGUUAAUUUUUGGAACUAUUGGGAUUUGUGACGCUUGUUGCAGUUUACCAAAACAAGUAUUUGAAAAUAUAUAGUAUCAACUGAAAUGUUUCCAUUCCGUUGUUGUAGUUAACAUCAUGAAUGGACUUCUUAAGCUGAUUACCCCACUGUGGGAACCAAAUUGGAUUCCUACUUUGUUGGACUCUCUUUCCUGAUUUUAACAAUUUACCAUCCCAUUCUCUGCCCUGUGAUUUUUUUUAAAAGCUUAUUCAAUGUUCUGCAGCAUUGUGAUUGUAUGCUGGCUACACUGCUUUUAGAAUGCUCUUUCUCAUGAAGCAAGGAAAUAAAUUUGUUUGAAAUGACAUUUUCUCUCAUAAAA